GAGUCCGGCGCGCAGAGGAGGAGGAGAAAGCUGACCGCUUAGGCCGGGGUAGUGGUCGUCGUGGUUUUCCUUGUAGUUCGUGGUCUGAGACCAGGCCUCAAGUGGAAACGGCGUCACCAUGAUCGCACGGCGGAACCCAGAACCCUUACGGUUUCUGCCGGAUGAGGCCCGGAGCCUGCCCCCGCCCAAGCUGACCGACCCGCGGCUCCUCUACAUCGGCUUCUUGGGCUACUGCUCCGGCCUGAUUGAUAACCUAAUCCGGCGGAGGCCGAUCGCGACGGCUGGUUUGCAUCGCCAGCUUCUAUAUAUUACGGCCUUUUUUUUUGCUGGAUAUUAUCUUGUAAAACGUGAAGACUACCUGUAUGCUGUGAGGGACCGUGAAAUGUUUGGAUAUAUGAAAUUACAUCCAGAGGAUUUUCCUGAAGAAGAUAAGAAAACAUAUGGUGAAAUUUUUGAAAAAUUCCAUCCAAUACGUUGAAGUCUUCAAAAUGCUUGCUCCAGUUUCACUGAUACCUGCUGUUUCUGAAUUUGAUGGAACAUGUUUCUUAUGACAGUUGAAGCUUAUGCUAAUCUGUAUGUUGACACCUUGUAAUUAAAAUACGUACCAUGAGUACUCUGACUCUUUAUUGUUGUAAGAAAAAUAGUUCAUCAUCAGAGAAUGGUCAGUUUCCAUUCACCCAUCUGAAAGAUUUUAAGAUGAGGUUGAAUUCUAGUUUAGAGUUAGCAGACUACCCAAAUCUGGCCCACUGCCAAUAAAGUCUCAUUGGAACACAGCCAUGCUCAUUUGUUUACAUGUUGUUUAUGGCGACUGCCAUGCUGCAAGAGCAGAAUUGAGUAGUUGUGAUAGAGACCUAUGGCCUGCAAAGCCUAAUUAAUAUGUAGCCCUUUCAGAAAAGGUUUGCCUGCCCCUGUCCUAGUGCAAAGUGAAUUUAGAGUGAGCCAGAUUAUGGAGGAUUCUGUGACUCUUGCCAAAUAAUUUUGACUUCAUCCUGUAGGUAUUAAGUCAUUAAGGCGUUUUAAAUCAUACAGUCAGGUUUGUAUUUCUGAGCUGUCUAUAAUGAAUGAUAUAGAAGGUGGUUUCGAAGGAGGAGACUCCAGACAAGGAAAACAGAAAUCUUAUGUUGCCAAGUUGUCUUUGCUCUUAGGUGGGUUAUCCUGGAGAAAAUGGACUCAGGAGCUAAUACUGUCUACAGUGGAGCUUGGUGCAAUUAGAAGCAAAAGACUGUACCUAACUGGAAUGAGGUUACUUUUUAUGGCUUAUCAAAUGCUUGUCCUGGCCCGAUGCAGUGGCUCAUGCCUGUAAUCCCAGCACUUUGAGAGGCUGAGGCAGGGCAGAUUGCAUGAGCCCAGGAGUUCGAGACCAACUUGGGCAACAUGGUGAAACACUGUCUCUACAUAAAAUACAAAAAUUAGCUGGGCGUGGUGGCACGUUCCUGCAAUCCCAGCUACUCAUAAGGCUGAGGUGGGAGGAUCUAUUGAGCCCUGGAAUUCGAGGAUGCAAUUAAUUGUGGUUGUGUCACAGUUCACUGCAGCCUGGGUGACACUCCAGCCUGGGUGACAAAGGAGACCCCGUCAAAAAAAAAAGUACUUGUCCCAAAAGUUUUUGUUUCCUAGCUUAGAAUUUAUAAUCAGAUUAGGUUUUGGAGAUAAAGUAUAUGUGGUAUUUUUUUUUUUUUUUUUGAGACGACAGUCUUGCUCUGUCAUCAGGCUGGAGUGCAGUGGCGCAAUUUCGGCUCACUGCAACCUCCACCUCCUGGGUUCAAGCAAUUCUCCUGCCUCAGCCUCCCGAGUAGCUGGGACUACAGGUGCAUGCCACGACGCCCAGCUGAUUUUUGUGUUUUUAGUAGAGACGGGGUUUCACCAUGUUGGCCAAGAUGGUCUCAAUCUCUUGACCUUGUGAUCCACCUGCCUUGGCCUUCCAAAGUGUUGGAAUUACAGGCGUGAGCCACCGCGCCUGGUCUAUAUGUGAUUUCAAAUUAGGUGGCCUUAUAAAUAUAAGCAGAUGGUUUCUGGGCAAAAUCAAAUGAUUUCUGUCUCUAUUUUCUUGAGUACCAAUUGUAAAAACUGAAAUUAGGUUGAGGAAAGUGCUUUAGAAAUAAUAAAGAUGUACAAAUACAAGGCUUUGGAUUUUUUAUUAGUUCUGCAAUAAAUAAUAGGUUUAUAGUUCA